AGCACAAGCCGUGCGCUCCCGGGCUGCGAGGUCUGGCUAGGCUACGGGCCACGCGCCGCCGCCGCUGCCGCCGCCACUGUCCUCUUCGGAGGCGCGGGCCCGACGGAAACCAUGUUUGUGGCUCGCAGCAUCGCGGCGGACCACAAGGAUCUCAUCCACGAUGUCUCUUUCGACUUCCACGGGCGGCGGAUGGCAACCUGCUCCAGCGAUCAGAGCGUUAAGGUCUGGGAUAAAAGUGAAAGUGGUGAUUGGCAUUGUACUGCUAGCUGGAAGACACAUAGUGGAUCUGUAUGGCGUGUGACAUGGGCCCAUCCUGAAUUUGGGCAGGUUUUGGCUUCCUGUUCUUUUGACCGAACAGCUGCUGUAUGGGAAGAAAUAGUAGGAGAAUCAAAUGAUAAACUGCGAGGACAGAGCCACUGGGUUAAAAGGACAACUCUGGUGGAUAGCAGAACAUCUGUUACUGAUGUGAAGUUUGCUCCCAAGCACAUGGGUCUUAUGUUAGCAACCUGUUCCGCAGAUGGUAUAGUAAGAAUCUAUGAGGCACCAGAUGUUAUGAAUCUCAGCCAGUGGUCUUUGCAGCAUGAGAUCUCAUGUAAGCUAAGCUGUAGUUGUAUUUCUUGGAACCCUUCAAGAAUAUCCAAACUGAUAGAAAAGAUGAAUAGAGCACAUUUAUACAACUUCCACAUCCCAAGCUCUCGUGCUCAUUCCCCCAUGAUCGCCGUAGGAAGUGAUGACAGUAGCCCCAACGCAAUGGCCAAGGUUCAGAUUUUUGAAUAUAAUGAAAACACCAGGAAAUAUGCAAAAGCUGAAACUCUUAUGACAGUCACUGAUCCUGUUCAUGAUAUUGCAUUCGCUCCAAAUUUGGGAAGAUCUUUCCAUAUUCUAGCAAUAGCGACCAAAGAUGUGAGAAUUUUUACAUUAAAGCCUGUGAGGAAAGAACUGACUUCCUCUGGUGGGCCAACAAAGUUUGAAAUCCAUAUAGUGGCUCAGUUCGAUAAUCAUAAUUCUCAGGUCUGGCGAGUGAGUUGGAAUAUAACAGGAACGGUGCUAGCAUCUUCAGGAGAUGAUGGGUGUGUAAGAUUGUGGAAAGCUAAUUAUAUGGACAAUUGGAAGUGUACUGGUAUUUUGAAAGGUAAUGGGAGCCCAGUCAAUGGGAGUUCUCAGCAGGGAACCUCAAAUCCUUCCCUAGGUUCAACUAUUCCAAGUCUUCAGAAUUCAUUAAAUGGAUCUUCUGCUGGCAGAAAGCACAGCUGAGUACAAGCUAACUGGAGUAACUUUGCUGUUUUGCUGCUUGUUGCAUGCACACAGGAAUGGAAAGCGAGCUCCUUUUCCCCUUCCCCAGCGCCGUUUGACCUCUCCCAAGAUACACCAGCAGCCUGCUUACUACUAAACGCAAUCCAAAAGGCCUUUAAAAAUACAGUGUAUAUUUUUUGUACUAGUCAGUUUAUUGACACUAUUUGAAACUUUUGAAAUAUAAACGGAGAGGCUUUCUGUUGAGACAUUGUCACCAAAACAAUUUUUUGAAAUGUUCCUGAAACUAAUUUGGGUUUAAAGAUUAAAAGGGUUGUUACCAUUCUUAUCUGAGUAGUUGGGAGGAGGGGAAUACCACUUUAGUUCAUUUGGAAAAUAUAGACAUAUUUCUUUUGCUUUCUUAAAACAGCUUAAAAUGAUGAACUUUUAUAAUUUUAAUUUGAAGAUUGAAUAAAUAUUUUUUAUAAAGAUUGUUUUGAGUGCUGAUUUGUUUACUUUUUGUAGAUUUGCUUUAUCCAUGAUAUUCAGUACAACUCUGUCAUUUCUUUGUAAUAUUUAAAAAAUAUUAGUAAAGGAGUGAAUUAAUAAAGUAGUAAUAGUAAAAUGAAAGGAACUUGACUGUACAGUUUGUAGCCAGGUUAAGCAUUUGGUAUUGUUUCAUUUACAAUUUGGGACUAAGAUGGAAACACUUUUUUUAUAAGUUUUUAAUUCAUAGUCACUAAAGAGAUAAAUGUUUCUUAUAUACAUUUGUGUAUUUUUAUGGUGUUAUUUAUUCCAUGGCUUAGCUUCCUUCAAAUCAAAAUUUGGACACACACUAUUAAGAGAAGCCAUUAAAAUUUUACUAAAAUUGUGCAUGUAAAUUAAUUGUCAGCAUUCCAUGUCUCAAGAUUUUCUUAAUUUAGUUCGCUGUUUAAAUUAAUUCAUGUCCUGUAAAGUUCUGACCUUGAUAACAAAGCUAUAAAUAUUUAAGUUUGCUAAUAUGCGUAAGUAUUAUCGGUAAGUUACAAGAUGGAAGAAGAAUAACAGUAGGGCACAGUCAUUCUGUGAAUCCUUUUACUUAUCAAAAUUUGGUAGCUAUUCUAAGGCUUUUGCAGAAAAAUAAGUGUUCAAUGUUUGUAGUUCUUCAAAAGCAUGUUGCAGUAGCCAGCCAUACUAUGUGUAUUCCCAGUAUCAUGUACGCACUAAAAAAAAUGUGUGCUUGCUGCUGCUGUGAGUGAACCAUUGCUUAAGAUAAAAAACUUAACUAGAUCUGUAAAUGUACAGAAUAGCAUCAGAUGUUUCUGAGAGAUUAGAAAAUGUUUUGAAUUUAUAAAAUUAAUGUUUUUCUUUGUAACAUUUAUAUAUAUUUUUUAACAUUUUAAGUUUAACAGAUUGUAUUCCUUUCAAGUUUCUAUACUUGCUUAAGCAAUCUUGAUUUGAGUAAGGGUCUUGAUUUGUGCUAUUAUGUUCUGUUAGUUUUGGCAUGAAUAUACUAAAGCUUUUUUUUUUUUUUCUAGCAUGUGUUUUCUCCUCUUUGGUUCUCUUUGUAUUUACUACUUUUCUCUUUUUCUUGUGUUUUUUUUUUCCUGUUUUUGUUUUGUUUGGUGUUUUGUUCCUGUCUUCAUUGUUUCAGGUAUUUCUUUACCCCUCUGGAUUCCCCACGGGCUGGAUCGAGAUGGUCCAGUUAUGCCCAGCUCCUUCCUCCUCCUCCUCCUCCUCUGGUAGAGCACUCUUGCGAUGCUGACACUGCCAACCUCCAGUAUCCUCACCCUCGCAGACGAUAUCUCUCUCGGCCUCUUAAUCCCUUACCUGAGAAUGAAGGGAUUUAAAACACUGAUUUAACAUUGAAAGGCCUUAUUCAAGUGCUUGUAAAUGCUUUCAUUUCUGGCUGCUUUUUGUUUUUCAUUUUCUUUCAGAAGAUUUUUCUAACUUAGGGUCUGUCUUGCAUGUAUUACAACCAGAAUACAGUGUUUGGAACCUAAAUCUGUUUGUGCGUCUGCAUCAAAGGAACAUUUGCUUCACUGGGUGAUAACCUUUGAUGAAAUGAGAUAUGUCCAAGUAACGUUAACUGUGAAGUUACACACAGUAGCUGACUUCAAAGUGCCUGUUCUGUAAAUUUUAUUUUAAACUGUUACCAUAGUCUUAAGUUGUUUAUGCUUUAUCAGACUGGCUAAUGUGAAAGCAUAAUAUUAUGAAGUUUAUUCUGCCUUAUGAGACCUUAAAAAAUGGAUUUCAUUUUACAGGCUAAUGUUGUAACUGACUAGUAUGUAAAAUAAAUCAUUCCUGUGUAUAAAGCAGCAAAACCUAA